AUCAUAUUUAAAAUCUGGGACAAAGAACCGUCGGGACGGAACUCCUUCCAUUGCAAAAGCUCGGCGCGGCCUCGGGAGCUGCCCGGCGGCCCCGGACCGAGGCAGCCCUCCCCUUUAAAAGAAGCGGAGGACAGGAUUGGGAUCCUUGAAACCCGAAACCCAGAAACAGCAUCGGAGCGGAAACCAGAGGGGAAACCUUGAACUCCUCCAGACAAUUGCUUCCGGGGAGUUGCGAGGGAGCGAGGGGGAAUAAAGGACCCGCGAGGAAGGGCCCGCGGAUGGCGCGUCCCUGAGGGUCGUGGCGAGUUCGCGGAGCGUGGGAAGGAGCGGACCCUGCUCUCCCCGGGCUGCGGGCCAUGGCCACGGCGGAGCGGAGAGCCCUCGGCAUCGGCUUCCAGUGGCUCUCUUUGGCCACUCUGGUGCUCAUCUGCGCCGGGCAAGGGGGACGCAGGGAGGAUGGGGGUCCAGCCUGCUACGGCGGAUUUGACCUGUACUUCAUUUUGGACAAAUCAGGAAGUGUGCUGCACCACUGGAAUGAAAUCUAUUACUUUGUGGAACAGUUGGCUCACAAAUUCAUCAGCCCACAGUUGAGAAUGUCCUUUAUUGUUUUCUCCACCCGAGGAACAACCUUAAUGAAACUGACAGAAGACAGAGAACAAAUCCGUCAAGGCCUAGAAGAACUCCAGAAAGUUCUGCCAGGAGGAGACACUUACAUGCAUGAAGGAUUUGAAAGGGCCAGUGAGCAGAUUUAUUAUGAAAACAGACAAGGGUACAGGACAGCCAGCGUCAUCAUUGCUUUGACUGAUGGAGAACUCCAUGAAGAUCUCUUUUUCUAUUCAGAGAGGGAGGCUAAUAGGUCUCGAGAUCUUGGUGCAAUUGUUUACUGUGUUGGUGUGAAAGAUUUCAAUGAGACACAGCUGGCCCGGAUUGCGGACAGUAAGGAUCAUGUGUUUCCCGUGAAUGACGGCUUUCAGGCUCUGCAAGGCAUCAUCCACUCAAUUUUGAAGAAGUCCUGCAUCGAAAUUCUAGCAGCUGAACCAUCCACCAUAUGUGCAGGAGAGUCAUUUCAAGUUGUCGUGAGAGGAAACGGCUUCCGACAUGCCCGCAACGUGGACAGGGUCCUCUGCAGCUUCAAGAUCAAUGACUCGGUCACACUCAAUGAGAAGCCCUUUUCUGUGGAAGAUACUUAUUUACUGUGUCCAGCGCCUAUCUUAAAAGAAGUUGGCAUGAAAGCUGCACUCCAGGUCAGCAUGAACGAUGGCCUCUCUUUUAUCUCCAGUUCUGUCAUCAUCACCACCACACACUGUGAUGUACGCUCUACACCCUUGAUCUUGAACACCCAAGAUGUGGCAGUGCGGCCCAGUUGAUGCUCAUCCCUGUUAACCCUGAUCAGGAUUUGCUUUGUACUGGCUGCUGGGUUGGAAAGUCACAAUCUUUGAAGAAAAGAAAAUGACCUAAAGUUAGACACAAGGUUCCAAAUUCAACAUUAAAUAAAUGAAGACCCCUGUUUUUUUCUCCUGAUUUAUAUGAAAAACAGCCUGACUGCAGUAGCAACAAGGUUCAAUAACUUUGAGCGGAUCCAUGUCAUAUCACUGUUUAGAGAAAUGCCAUUUGAAUGAAACCUGAAAUUCAACAAACUGAGACCUGAAACAUCAAAGCGAAAACAACUGCUCUAUAACUGCAGGAUAAUGGAGGAAUUAAGAAUACAGGAUAUUGAGUCGAAAAUCUUUAUUUCACAUCCCAGCCCCUUGACUUUCCAGGGUGAUCCUGGACAGGUUUACCUGGAGUCUGUUUCAGAACCUGUCUCGCAUUUUUAUAGUAAAGAUUAAGUAUAUAAGGGGCUUGAGGUACAUAAUAGUCUGUUCAAAAAAUGACAGCUGUGUAUUAGGUUAUUGACCUAACUUUCCUUGCCAAGUAAAAGUCUAAUGCCCUGCCCCAUUAGAUUCACUGUACAUGUCCCGUGGCUUAUAAACAGGCUAUCUCCCCCUGAUUAAGAAGCAUGCUCCUUUUGAGUCUCUACGAUAAGACUGUAUUUUAGGAGCAGGCUGGAAAAAAUCUUUGAAGAUGUUGCCCACAAGAUAACUAGGAAGAAAAACACCAGUAAAUCAGAUGUGGUGAUAAGUCAAACAAGACUGGGUGGCAGGCUGACUCUUUGCUACUUUUGAAGAGUUUUCCUCAAUAAAUGAAUCAAGUAAAUAGUAACAUAGGGAAAUAUUUAGACAAAUUAAACACAUGAAUUAAAGCAAAUAAAGUUGAUACAUUAUUACCACAUGCAAAAUUUCUGUUGCCACAAAAAAAAAUCUAUCAUGCAUUCAGAAUCUUGGGAUUCUUAAAUGUUCUUUUGUUCUAUUCUAUAUGUACUUUCUUUGGGGCCCCUCUUUCUGAUAUAAAGAUAGGAAUUUGCCUAAAAAAAUAAUUUUAGCUCAAGAUGACAAGCCUAGGGACCUUCUCACUUAUAUGUUGCCAGACAAAGACUCCAAAAUUUUGUCUCCAAAUUCCUCUUUUCCAUAUUCCAAGUCGUGCCUUCACUUCCUCCUCUCAUGCAAAGGCCUGGAGAGCCACAGACUUGUUCAUUAUUUCAGGAAGAAAGACCCUCUUAACAUCCGGGUUAUUUUCAACACUUCAUGACUACCAAUGUUUCACAGGAAGGCGGGCCUCCGGCUGCCAUAUAGAGGUAGUUUAUAGCUUUGGAAACAACUAGAGAGUUGUCAUAAAGCAAACGCAGACAUUGGAAAGAGCGGUUGUCUCUCAGGCAUAGUAUCGCCCCUAUGUUUCUUGAGGCAAAACAGACCAUCUUGUUCACCGUCACAACCCAGCACCUGGCACAAUGUCUGCACAUACUCAUUACUCAGCAAAUAAUGAUGGUUGAGUGAAUAAAUGAAUGAACCCAAUCAAGGGUCAUACUGGUACCAUGAUGGCACCUACUGGCAGGAAAGAAAAGGAGCCAGAAGGAGGUAGAAUCAGAACAGGGGGCUCUGAGUUGGUUGGGAGGUAGACUUCAGAAAAGGAUGGCCAGCAAUUCUAUCUUCAUAUCCAAGGAGCUUGAGCAUAAUUUAACAGGGGAAAAAAUCUGCCAGGUAAGAAACUAUAACCAGCGUUCCCAGGAAGGGCAAUAGUCAAAGAUAUCAUCAUAAAAGCACCAGCUCCAGUAGGAGCAGACCCCUGCCUGGGGUGCAGACUUGGUAGAAGGGUGUAGAAAUAGCCCACUAACUGGAUCAAGAUUCUGGGCAGGCCUCUAGUCUGUGAGGAUCUGCAGCACAAGGUUGGAAGCCAAGCAGAACCAUAGAGACUGAUAGACUCAAGAUCACUCCAGAAAAGCUGUGACCCAGGGAACAUUGGCAUGGCCUGAGCUCACCCUGGAAUACCAGAAACAUAGAUUACAGCAGUUCAGCUAAUCUGGAUGCUGCCAGCUGGGGCUGAGGAUGCACAGUCUGCUUUAGUGAGUACUGGCUCAGAAGAGGAUGUGCUGGAGCCCAGAGAUAGAGGCCACAGUGACUGCAGGUAAAAGACAGCAGAGGAGGGCAGUGACCAUCCCCCGCACAGUCUUUGGAGGAAAUUUCCAGGUGUCUGUUUUCUAAGUCAGUUCAUUUCCAUUACCAGUUGCUUUAAAGCGAUGAGAGAAUACAAAUCCAGCCUGGUUUUGUAGUCAUUAUGACUCUUUAGGUAAACAGACAGCUGGCAUGGCUGCCCUUGCCAAAAUCUCUUGAAUUUCACCAGCCCGGUAGGGAGUGAAUUCAGUAGCCUGUGCUGAGUGGCAAUCUCACCUUCCAACAUAAUAAAAAAUUAUUGCGUACUCUUCAGAGAAAGUAGAAAUCAGAGACAUUUUUGUCUUCUAUUUCUUUUCCAAGGUCAGCAAACAGUCCAUCAAUCAAGUGGGUAGCUGUCUUUGGGACAGACAAUUCAUUCCAGUGCUUUAUGCAUGUGGGCCUCUUUACUAAGGAAAGAAGGAUGGGGAGGAGGUUGCUGGUAGCAAAUGGAGCCAAUGAUAUCAUAACAAUCAGGACCAACGUGUUUUAAAUCUAUACUCUGGGCAAAGUGUUAGGGACUCGAAGAAUAGCCAGUCCUUGCCCUCCAGAGGCUUACAAUACAGUUGCCAAGGCAGGAUAUAUUACUUAAAGAGGUAAAUAUUAUACAAUUUGGGGUAUAAAAGCAAAUAUCACACAGGUACCCUAAAAUUCCCCACCUGUUCCAAAGACUCGUGAACCUUUAGAUAAGUCAAUGGACACAAACAUGGCACGCUCUGAGGAGUGUCCACUUCAUGGGCCUGGUGAGUUACUUCCCAGUUACCUAAGAAGGAUUUUCACCCCUUCUGCAAAGCGAAGCUGGACAGAUUAUUCCAGAAAUUCAGGUAUAACAAGUAGGCAGCUCAUGAUUAGCUCAGUCCCAAAACUCUAUCCCAUGAGUGUAUUUUCCCCAACAAGGAUCUCCCCAAACUGUUUCUCAAUACCAGGAAACAACCUCUGAAGAAAAGAAGACCCUUCCAAACAACCAGUUGCAGAGAACAGAAUCAGGACUCACUAACUGACUUUCCCCUGUAGGUUCCUUCGCCCCAACAAUAUUAUUCCACUUCCUGUCCAACUUUCCCACACCCACCGCUUCUUACUCAUUCAGUGUCACAUAACCUGGAAGAAUGAGGCAAAACUGAACUGGAAGGGAGAUUGGAGACUCACCUUGAAGAGGGUUUGAAUGACAGAAUAUGGAGUUUGGGCAACGGGAAGCCAUUUGAGGGAAGCACAAUGCAUUAUUUUAGGAGGCUUAAUUUAGCAUGUGUAUGCUUUAAGUAUAUUAGUAACAAAAUGGCAUUAAUUUGGAUGCCACUGAUUUGUGAAUUUGGUCAUCUGGAAAAGGAGUAGGCUCUAGUUUACUUUUCCAUUAUUUGAGCUAAAGGAACUUAGUACCAAGAGUGACCAAUCCACAGCAUUGGGGCUACAAGUGAAUCAGAGCCUCAUACUCAGCCCUUGAAAAAGCAUAGCCACUGACGCACUUUGUUAUUGCUGUAAUUAUAGGUGAUAGGUCCUUUGAAAUAUGUGGCUUAGCAAAACACAGAGGAAAGACUUGAGAGGAAAAGUGGGCUUUGGGAUCAGAUCAAUGUGGCUAAAAUCAUGGUUCUGCUGCUUACAGGGUGUAUGACUUUAGACUGAAAUAAUGUACUUAGAAGAGCUGACAUGGGGCCUGGCACACAGUAGAUGCCCAAUCUUAGUUUUCUUGUACUGAUGUUGUGGUCUCUAUAUGAAUUUGUGCAGUGAGAUGGUUUCCAAAGCCUCUGACUUCUGGUUGAAUUAGCAGAAGUAUAGUAUCUGAAACUAAGGAGGUGAUGGGACCUCUCAACUUGGUGAAGUUAAAAUCUCCGUUCGAAUAUUGUGUUCAGUACCAAGGACACUCCAAGGGAGAACAUAGAGAAACUGAGUGUAUGAGAAAUACUACCAAAUACGGUAUGUUAUGUAGAAUAUAGAAUUGGGGCUCUUUAGCCUGGGGCAUACUUAGCAUAGAGACAAUAUUCAAAGGGCUGCGCUGAAACACAUGCAGCUAUACCUUUAGAGCCCUAAUUCUACAGAUUAUUUGUUGUAUAGAUCCAAGGGGUAGAAUAGGCUCAAAGGAACAGUUUCUGGCUUCGUUUUUAAAAAGGCCUUUUUAAUUAGCUGCAUUGGGUGGGAAUGAGCUCGCUAUUAUAGUUGCAGUCAAGCACAGGCAGCAGGACAACUUGGCAGAAUAAUGUAAUCACCAUUCAUGCCUCAGAGUGGGGAUUGGAAUAGAAAAGCUUUCAGACUCCUUAUGCUGCUGAGAGGCUGUGACUGUAGACCUAAAAGUAUGUUAGGAAAGGAGUAAACUAAAUACUACCAGUCCUAUACAGUAUCACAAAUAAGUUUGGUUCUUACAUCUUGAAAAUGAAUCUAAGAGAGCUCUGUUGGUGAUACUGGAGACAACUUCUCUUAGUGCAGUUCAGAUUGGCCAACCUCCACCUAAUACAAGUGGGAUCAUAUUUCAGACCAGAGUACUUCAAACUCCUGAGAAUAAUCUGUUUUCAAGUAAUCUCAAAACACACCCUGUAAUUUACAAACAACACAUUAGUCCCAAAUCAGUCUCCUCUAUUUAUUAGCCAGUCUCCAUAGAGCCAUACAUAACUCAAGGUAUUUUUUUUACAAUGUCCCAGUAUUUUUAUUAUUAUGAUUACUAUUAUUAUUAUUUUAACAGGAUGGCUUGUGGUUUUACAUACAAUCAUUAGAGACGGUAAAAGACCACAGGAAUAUCAGAGUGCGGAACUCAGAUCUCAAAUAUUGUUUAUGAACUGAAAUAAAAGUAGUUUGCCAACAUCUCUAUUUUGACAACCCUUGUAACCCUUAUAUGUAUAAAAAUAUCUUUUAAAAGAUGUUUUGGAUGA